GUUGUUGCUGCCGCGAUGCUGGUGGCGGCGGCCGCGGAGCGGAACAAGGAUCCCAUCUUGCACGUGCUGCGGCAGUACCUGGAUCCGGCCCAGCGUGGCGUCCGCGUCCUCGAGGUGGCCUCGGGCUCCGGCCAGCACGCAGCGCACUUCGCGCGGGCCUUCCCCCUGGCCGAGUGGCAGCCGUCGGACGUGGACCAGCGCUGCCUGGACAGCAUCGCGGCCACCACGCAAGCCCAGGGCCUGACCAACGUGAAGGCCCCGCUACACCUGGACGUGACGUGGGGCUGGGAGCACUGGGGCGGGAUCCUGCCACAGUCGCUGGACCUGUUGCUCUGCAUCAACAUGGCCCAUGUCAGCCCCCUGCGCUGCACGGAGGUCUGUGGGGAGCCCAGCAUGGGUGUCUGCCGUGGCACCACUCACCCUGCAUGGGGGCAGCUGGGAUGCCAGAUUUGCCCCCAUCACAGUCGGGGGGCUCUUCAGAGCAGCAGGACACCUGCUCAAACCCAGGGCCCUGCUCAUCACCUACGGGGGAGGGGGUGCCCUUUCAUUCUCCAAACCCCAGCCUGCAAGUCUGUCCCAGGCUCUCUGGGAAAUACCCCGACCUUGGUCCAGUGGGCUGUGUCCCCAUGCCCACAGCCCUAUGCCAUCAAUGGGAAGAUCUCCCCCCAGAGCAACGUGGACUUUGACCUGAUGCUCAGAUGCAGGAACCCAGAAUGGGGGCUUCGGGACACAGCCCUCCUGGAGGACCUGGGAAAGGCCAGUGGCCUGCUCCUGGAGAGGAUGGUGGACAUGCCAGCCAACAACAAAUGCCUGAUCUUCCGGAAAAACUAAGCCCCUCCUUCACCCCCGCACACCUGCAUCCCUGCCGGAGGCUCUGUGAGGCACGAACCCUGCCUCCCUAGGCCGGACCUUGUGGACGACAGCCCCACCCAGUCUGUGCUCUCAGCCGCUGGCCGAAGGGCCCAGCCUGCUCAGAAUAAAGCAUGUCCUGCUGCCGG